GUCACGGCGGCGGAGGGCGCAGGCGGCUGGGCGCCUGGCGAGUGGACUGUUCGAGCCCUUCCGCUGGGACCCGGGCCCUGGCUCCGGCCCCGCGAUGGGAGCUGCUCUCCGCGGGCUGAGCCUGUCAGCAUCCUCGACGCACCCUGGUCCCUGAAGUCGGAGAAGAGCCCCUACCCACCCACACCCCCUUGCCCCAUUUUGGGUCGCCUGGGUCCUCAGUCCUAGCGGAUCCUCAGUCCUAGCGGCCACCGGGUCUGAAAGGAGCAAGACGAUGAUCCUGGCGUCGGUGCUGAGGAGCGGUCCCGGGGGCGGGCUUCCGCUCCGGCCCCUCCUGGGACCCGCACUCGCGCUCCGGGCCCGCUCGACGUCGGCCACCGACACACACCACGUGGAGAUGGCUCGGGAGCGCUCCAAGACCGUCACCUCCUUUUACAACCAGUCGGCCAUCGACGCGGCAGCGGAGAAGCCCUCAGUCCGCCUAACGCCCACCAUGAUGCUCUACGCUGGCCGCUCUCAGGACGGCAGCCACCUUCUGAAAAGUGCUCGGUACCUGCAGCAAGAACUUCCAGUGAGGAUUGCUCACCGCAUCAAGGGCUUCCGCUGCCUUCCUUUCAUCAUUGGCUGCAACCCCACCAUACUGCACGUGCAUGAGCUAUAUAUCCGUGCCUUCCAGAAGCUGACAGACUUCCCUCCGAUCAAGGACCAGGCGGACGAGGCCCAGUACUGCCAGCUGGUGCGACAGCUGCUGGAUGACCACAAGGAUGUGGUGACCCUCUUGGCAGAGGGCCUACGUGAGAGCCGGAAGCACAUAGAGGAUGAAAAGCUCGUCCGCUACUUCUUGGACAAGACGCUGACUUCGAGGCUUGGAAUCCGCAUGUUGGCCACGCAUCACCUGGCGCUGCAUGAGGACAAGCCUGACUUUGUCGGCAUCAUCUGUACUCGUCUCUCACCAAAGAAGAUUAUUGAGAAGUGGGUGGACUUUGCCAGACGCCUGUGUGAGCACAAGUAUGGCAAUGCGCCCCGUGUCCGCAUCAAUGGCCAUGUGGCUGCCCGGUUCCCCUUCAUCCCUAUGCCACUGGACUACAUCCUGCCGGAGCUGCUCAAGAAUGCCAUGAGAGCCACAAUGGAGAGUCACCUAGACACUCCCUACAAUGUCCCAGAUGUGGUCAUCACCAUCGCCAACAAUGAUGUCGAUCUGAUCAUCAGGAUCUCAGACCGUGGUGGAGGAAUCGCUCACAAAGAUCUGGACCGGGUCAUGGACUACCACUUCACUACUGCUGAGGCCAGCACACAGGACCCCCGGAUCAGCCCCCUCUUUGGCCAUCUGGACAUGCAUAGUGGCGCCCAGUCAGGACCCAUGCACGGGUGAGACCCUGCCAGGCCAGGAUGGAGGGGUGGGGGACCCCAGGAGACUCAAGCCUCUGAAGCCUCCUGUCCUGUCCCCCUGCCCACCCCCAGCUUUGGCUUCGGGUUGCCCACGUCACGGGCCUACGCGGAGUACCUCGGUGGGUCUCUGCAGCUGCAGUCCCUGCAGGGCAUUGGCACGGACGUCUACCUGCGGCUCCGCCACAUCGAUGGCCGGGAGGAAAGCUUCCGGAUCUGACCCCACAGCCUUUGGCCUGCUCACCCGACCAGCCUGGGCCGCAUUCCCUGCAGGACCUCCCGGGUCAGGCAGGGCGGCCCCCUGCUCCACACACUGCUGCAUCUUGGGUCUCAGGGACCCAGACAGAUGGACUUACAUGGAGCUGGGCACUGCCCUGCCUCAACAGGGUCCAUUGCCUCCUCGCCUCCAGAACUUGGAGCAGGGAAGUGGGCACCCUGAGGCCUCCAGCACCAGUUCCGUCAUUCUCGUUCCUGGGGAACCCCCACUCUGACCUGUUAUUAAAGUUCACAUUUUGAAUGCCCUCUCGGGCCCCGUGUGUGGGGAGGGCAGGUGAACUUUUGUUUCUGCCCCCAUUCAGGUUCACUGAGCCCUUGGGUUGAACUGGUUCGUGUCCCAGUCUCUUACCUGCCCUGAGAGCCUGGCAGGCCAGGAGUAGAAUGGGUCCCAAGUCUGUUGCAUGUUUGAUUUGGUGGGAGUGGGAUGACUGCAGCACCUUAUACAAAGAGCUUUCAUUCAUCUUGUUGAACAAAUGUUUCCGGGUCCCAGAUAAUAUUGAAGGCCCAGACUGACCCA